AGUCCGCGCCGCAGGUGGUGCUUGUCUGCAGAGUCAUGACCUCUUUCCGCUUGGCCCUCAUCCAGCUUCAGAUUUCUUCCAUCAAAUCAGAUAACGUCACUCGCGCUUGUAGCUUCAUCCGGGAGGCAGCAACGCAAGGAGCCAAAAUAGUUUCUUUGCCGGAAUGCUUUAAUUCUCCAUAUGGAGCGAAAUAUUUUCCUGAAUAUGCAGAGAAAAUUCCUGGUGAAUCCACACAGAAGCUUUCUGAAGUAGCAAAGGAAUGCAGCAUAUAUCUCAUUGGAGGCUCUAUCCCUGAAGAGGAUGCUGGGAAAUUAUAUAACACCUGUGCUGUGUUUGGGCCUGAUGGAACUUUACUAGCAAAGUAUAGAAAGAUCCAUCUGUUUGACAUUGAUGUUCCUGGAAAAAUUACAUUUCAAGAAUCUAAAACAUUGAGUCCGGGUGAUAGUUUCUCCACAUUUGAUACUCCUUACUGCAGAGUGGGUCUGGGCAUCUGCUACGACAUGCGGUUUGCAGAGCUUGCACAAAUCUACGCACAGAGAGGCUGCCAGCUGUUGGUAUAUCCAGGAGCUUUUAAUCUGACCACUGGACCAGCCCAUUGGGAGUUACUUCAGCGAAGCCGGGCUGUUGAUAAUCAGGUGUAUGUGGCCACAGCCUCUCCUGCCCGGGAUGACAAAGCCUCCUAUGUUGCCUGGGGACACAGCACCGUGGUGAACCCUUGGGGGGAGGUUCUAGCCAAAGCUGGCACAGAAGAAGCAAUCGUGUAUUCAGACAUAGACCUGAAGAAGCUGGCUGAAAUACGCCAGCAAAUCCCCGUUUUUAGACAGAAGCGAUCAGACCUCUAUGCUGUGGAGAUGAAAAAGCCCUAAAGUUUAUGUUUCUAAUGUGUCACAGAAUAGGACGAUAUGAUUCUACAACAUAAUCAACUCCCUAUUAAAUUCUUUAAUGAAGAUUUUUUUUUUAAUUCGGCCUUGUCCUUCCUAGGUUCUCUAUUGAGAUGAGAAAGCCUCAUUAUGCUGACAUUUUCCACGCCACAUUAAAUAGUUAAAAAGGAUGCAGCCUGGAGCCAGAGAGCAGAAAGCUGGGCUGGUUCUGAAGCUUCUUCCAUACUUAAGUUGCCUCCAAGCAGUUUGUGAAAGUAUCAGAUCUUGGUAUCCUGGUGAUUGAUUCACCUAAUAUAAAUAUAUUUGUGUCAUGAACCUCUUAUCCCGUUGCUGGAGUUGUAAUCUCCAUCAUCUAGAAAACGUGGUCUGGUGCUAUUCUUUUCCAAGCAGUACCUUGAAGUUCCAUUUUUGGUUCAUGAGUAGCUAUAGAACGCAAGGUGAUACAUCUUUGGUGUUUGCCAGAGAAGUUGGCAGCCCCACCCCUCCUACCAGCCUUUGCACUCUUCAAAUUUAAAAAGGAGCUACUUAUCAACCCCAGGCCCUUCUGGUCUUAGAGGAAGGACUGGGCCAACAAAGAGCACCAUGGGAGAAUGGCAGUGGUGGCAUUUAGUGAAGACAAUUUAGUAUGAAUGUCUGCAAAAGAUUUUUUUGAUAGCGUUGAGUGUCUGAAAGUCCCAUUAUUUUUCUUUUUUCUUUUUCCCCAGUAACACUUUCUAGCUCCACGGAUAAGGAAUCACUGAACCUAGUAGUUCUUAGACAGCUUGGUUUGAGAAUCCUUUUGCGGUUAAAAAUUAGGGACUGAGCCAGGCGCAGUAGCAUGCGCCUGUAGUCCUAGCCACAUUGGAGGCUGAGGUAGGAGGAUCCCUUGAGUCCACAAGUUUGAGUUCAGCCAGAGACCCUAUCUCACUAUAUAUAUGUAUCUCAAAGACUUCAAUGGGUUUUUGCUUACAUGGGCCAGUAAUUGUUGAACAACCAGCUAUUUGAGAAAAAGCCCUGAUUUUGCUGCUUUUCAUGGUGUAAAUACUUAACCAUGGCUGAGUUUGAGCUAUCUGCAUGACACCUCUAAACACAGAGUUGGGAAUAGAUGUGCACAAUCAGCUCUGGGGAGCUGGUGCAAUCCUGCCCUAGCACACCACUGGUUUAAGAUAGAUAUAUCAUAUAGAUAUUUACCAUUUACCAUAUUGGAAAGUAAAAUGGAGAAAAAUUUAAAACACAAGAUACAUGAGCACACAUUCCAUUAGCUAUUAAGGUGAUGGACACGGUGUCCAAAUGACACGGUGUCAUUUAACUUCUGGAAAACAACACUGUGUACUGAGAACAAGAGAAAGACAAAUGACUUUUUUAAAUUAAGUUUUUAAUUUACAAUUGAUGCAUAAUUUUACUUUAAAAAAAUAAGUGUGCAAUUUGGUAAACUUUGACAUAUACAGCUAUAAACCACUCCAAUCAAGAUAACAUAUUUACCACCCCCAACAGUUUCCAUGUGCUGUAUUAUAAUCCCUCUGGCUAGUCCUUUGUCAAUCACUGAUAAAUUUUAUUACUAUAGAUUAGCUUGCAUUUUCUAAAAUUAUAUAAAAAUGAAAUCAUGCCAUUAGUGCUUUUUCUGUAUGUCUUCUUUCACUCAAAAUCACUUGGAACUCAAAAUUACUUCUUUCACUCAAAAUCACUCAAAAUUACAUACUCUGUAUGUCUUCUUUCACUCAAAAUUACUUCUUUCAUUUUUAGACGGAAGCAUUUAGACCUCAAAAUUACUUGGAGAUUCAUCUGGUAUGUGCAUUAAUAAUUCAUAAUUCAUUCCUUUUUUAUUGCUGAGUAGUAUACAAUUUGUUUAUCCAUUUAUCUGCUGUUGGAGAUUUGGGCUAUUUCCAGAUUUUGGCUGUUGCAAAAAAGCAACCUCACAGAUCCUUUUAAAGGAUGUCAGGUGCUUUCAGGUAACCCUAGACUAUAGUACCACUGCUCUCUAUCCUAGCAGGCACACUGAAAGUUAAACCUUGUAAUAGUGCGAAAUCAUUUUCUUUUUUAAAAAUAUAUUUUCUUACUUUUAUAUAUUUUACUCAAUCUCAUGACAGAUUACAUUUUCUUUUUUAAAUAGAAAGUCUUACUGUAAAGCCCACAUCUGUAUAAAAAAAUGAAAGAAUGAUCUGGUUGAUGUGGAUGUGUGGAACCUAGGAACCUUCUCUUGGAUUUUCUCUUAUUCCCCAAAAAACUUCAUUUCCUCUAAAGAGCUGCUCAGAAGUUUGAAAACCAGUGGACAAGCCAUCCUAGCUGUCUUGAUGCUAGAGAAGCAAAGACGCUUUACAGAGAUGUAGCAUUCCUGUAACAGGUAAGGCAGGUGGAUGCUAAACUUUUUACAUUUCUUUUUUUUUUUUUUUUUUUUUUGAGACAGAGUCACGCUGUCGCCCAAGCUGGAGUGCAGUGGCAUGAUCUUGGUUCACUGCAUCCUCUACCUCCUUGGUUGAAGCAAUUCUCAGGCCUCAGCCUCCUAAAAGUAGCUGAGACUACAGGCACGUGCCACCAUGCCUGGCUAAUUUUUGUGUUUUUAGUAGAGAUGGGGUUUCACCAUCUUGGCCAGGCUGGUCUUGAACUCCUGACCUCAAGUGAUCCACCUGCCUUAGCCUCCCAAAAUGCUAGGAUUAGAGGCGUGAGCCACCGCGCCCGGCCUAAUUUUUGUAUUUUUAGUAGAAAUGGGGUUUCACCAUGUUGGCCAGUCUGAUCUCGAACUCCUGGCCUCAAGUGAUCCACCAGCCUUGGCCUCCCCAAAGUGUUGGGAUUACAGACGUGAGCCACGGCACCCAGCCUUUUGUUUGUUUUUGUUUUUAUGUAUUUCAUUAAAUGAAUUGUCCUUUUAGUGGUAUAUCAGGAGAUCUUGCCUUCUGGUACUCUUGAAAAAUAUGAAAAGAAACAACUGAAGUAGGCAUCUCCUAUAAUUAGUAUGUAGCAUUUUAUUCUCAGAAAAUGUGUGGUAACCUGGCCCUGGAUUUUACCUUUUUGCAAAGUGAUAUCCGAAUAAAAUGAACACUAGAUUCCCACUUGGAGUGGAAGAACAUUGCAGUUGAGGCCUUGGGUAAGUUUUAACUGCCAUACCCCUGUACUCCCCGACUUUCUAAUGAAUUAGACAAUGAUGUUUUAUUUUUGUUUUUUGUUUUUGCAUAAUACUUUGAAGUCUGCUAUCACAAGUUGUGAACCUCUAUCUCUUGCAGUUUAGGUAAGGCAACACAUUUAAUGAAUUCACAUUUAAGUGAAUUCCUCACAGGGAUGACGACCUCUGUUGAAAUAGGUCAGGAUGUGCAGUUUGUGGUGAAAGUUCUACUUGACUUUGACCUAGCUGUUUGAAGCUGAGAGCUAACAGAUAAUAAGUGUUGCACUGGUUGCAAAUGAAUAAAUAAGUAACAUUAUGGGGUUUUAAAUGACCAAGGAGUAGAUUGUGACAUCGACUGGGUAUUUAGGGAAGGACUCCUUCCUGAUACCAAAAGUUAGGUCUGUGCAAAGUACACCAAGUGGAAAAAAGUUUAGACAAGAGUUUAGGUUUCAAGAUAAAUGUUCUGCUCUAUUGGCACUGGUUUUAAGUCUUUUGUGCUACUUUUUAGGCAUUGCUGUGUAAGUUUUGGUGGUGCGUGGGUACAAUGAAGCCAGGAGGGAUAGAAAGGGAAAUGAUGUGUGUGCUGCAGGCUAAACAGGGGCUCUUCCUUAUGCCUCAUAACCACCUGUGUGUGACAGUUUCACAUUUCCUAUCAAAUUAUUAUCUUCAUUCAUUUCUACUUGUGAAUGAAGUUCGGAGACUAAGAAAAAGCCAGCUGUUGGAAUAGAAAGCACUUUAGGAUAAAAUGGUCUUGUUAAAAUCACCAAUUAAAAAGUUAAGCCCCUGAUGUACAAAUAACUAAAACACAUACAUACAAAGACAGUGCUUCUUGUUCAAUGAUUUACUUCACAGCUGAUUCAUAAUCAAAUGAACAAGAAUCUGCAAGAACAGAACAUGGUGGGCAGGGUCCAGUAAUUCCAAAUGUUGUCAUCCUAGCUCUUCCUGAAGCAUAUUGAAUCCUCCAAGUAUAUCCCGUUGUGCUAACUAGGCUUUAAGUCUUUUGUCUGUAGAUUCAUUCUCAAAGUUUCUCCCUCAGAACAAAGAGCACGCCAUCCUGUAAAGUACUCUUCCUGAUUUUUUUUCACCCAAUUUCUUAGUUUCUUUCAAUUGCUUUUCAGACCCCGGCAGGCAGAUUCUGCCCUCAUCUGUCCAGUGACACUCUUCUGGCAGAUUACUAAAGACCGAUUUGUAGACCUGUCCAUGUGGCCUCUCUCAACACCAUUGGUGUGACCUUGCUCAUACUGCCUCUCUCACCACUUAACAUUGUCCCUUAGAUGUUAAAGGCCCUUAUAUUAAUAGUUUUAUUUUAGCUCCUUUACAUUUUAUUUUGUCCUGAGGAAUCUCAGCUACAUGCAUGGUCUUCAAUAUAUGCCGAUAAUUCUCAUUCACAUAGCUCUCCUGUUGGCUUUUCCCCACUCGUUUAAAAACAACCACUUCACUUUGCUGGACUCUACCUUGAAUGCCUCAUUUUCAGCUCACACUCAUGCUGUGCCUUUAUUUAGAUUUGUUGUGGUUGUUUCCCCACAUUCUGGAAGCUCCUUACCUAAAUCCUGUUUAUUCCUUAAUGCUUAGCACAAUUUAUUACUCUUGUUUCCAUGGCACUACAUUGUACUUCUGUUUUAGAGACUACCUUCCUCUGAAGCAUAUGACAGGUUCAUUUACUAUCCAGCCCACCAAAACUCAGUUUUUGAGCUCCUCUAUGUUCAUCUUUUUAUGGCUAACCCUCACCAUCAUGAGUGCUUAGUAAAUGUUGAGUUGGAAUGAAUUUAUUCCUACAGGUUGCACUUGCUCUCUCACCAAGUGUUCUGGCCAAAUAAUUCUGGAAUGAUUUCCUUACCUUAAGGGAGUCUGAUCUGGGAAGAGCCUGGGACGUGAUGUAACUUCAUAUGCUGUAGAGCUGAAUAUUCAUUUACUUAAGAUCUUAGCUCCAUUAGAAAGCAGUGAAAGCAGUGUUAAUUCAGAGGCCGGGUAUGGUGGCUCACGCCUGUAAUCCCAGCACUUUGGGAGGCCAAGAUGGGCAGAUCACUUAAGGUCAGGAGUUCAAGACCAGCCUGGCCAACAUGGCAAAACCCCAUCUCUACUAAAAAUACAAAAAUUAGCCGGGUGUGGUGGCACAUGCCUGUGAUCCCAGCUACUCGGGAGGGUAAGGCAGGAGGAGGUUACAGUGAGCCAAGAUCACACCACUGUACUCCUGGGCAACAGAGUUAAACUGUAUCAAAAAAAAAAUGCAGUAUUGAUUUAGAGCUAAGGUCACCUGAUGCUCAGGCCAGUAAUUUCUCCCUGCAUCAUGCUGUUGUCUAAGGCAGACACUGUAAAGCUCUACACUGCUGAAAAACUAAGCUUGAGAUGCAUAAAAGAACACAUAGAGAUGGGGAGUCAGUUCUCCAUACAUUUUGUGAGUAGAGGCAUUGGUGUUUUGUUCCAAACUAUCCAAUCGAGAAUGUUCAUAUAAUGACAGCUUUGGAAGGUAGAGACUAUCUUCCUCUGGAUCAUAGGACAGGUUUGUUUACUAUCUGAUACAGUCAAAAUAGUGUUUCCCUCUAAUGCGAAAGUCAGGCCAGUUUGCUUGUGACCUCAUUAGAUUUGGGCUGUGACGCAAACCCACUGCAUGUGCAGUAUCCACCUAGCUUGCCCUGUGUCACUCCCAUGGGAUCUGUGGCUCAAACUCAUGUUGCUUGCUAUGUUCUAAAUAAUUAAGUCUGUUGUCUGACCCAGGAGUCUCAUGUCUUCUGCCAGCAUUCAGAAAACUAGUUUUCAAGAAGGGUAACAUCUUAGACCUUUUACAGCUCUUGACACAGAGCAAUAUUGAGAAAUAAAAUCAGGUAAAAGUUAUUUAAUAUAGCAGUUCAUAAUUUAGGCCAUGGAUCAUCUCUGCAGAGAAUCCUACCAUGCUGCAUUCUUGCUUUAAACCUUUCGCCCUCUAAAACAAUGCCCAAGAGCCAAUGUUAGUCAUGGUCUUCCUGUAUUUGCUCUAGGUAAGCUGUUUCAUAGCCUUCCAGGACAACACUUGCACAGGUUAUCUUUAAGCACCAACAAAAGAAAUGGAGAAAUUUGAGCCAUGUAUCCUGAGCUCUGAAAGGCAGCAAUCAUCUUGACCCCAAGCAUACACCAUGUUCAGCUUCCUCCCCUUGGCCAGGUACCACAGCUACUUCUAUCCCAGUGAUCAGCAGGCCCUCCAGCAUGAAGACCUUUGAGAAGGAUCUAUAGCUGUCAACUCCUAAUAUGAUUUGUGCACUAUCACCUUGAAGUAAACCAGACUAGUUAUUUUCAUGCUAA